AGAUCUGAGCACCCAGCCACCUUCACGCCACCGCCCAGCUGCCCAGGAGCCCAGCCAGGACUGGCCAUACUGCCACCGACACGUGCACACACGCCAACAGGCAUCUGCCAUGCUGGCAUCUCUAUAAGGGCUCCAGUCCAGAGACCCUGGGCCAUUGAACUUGCUCCUCAGGCAGAGGCUGAGUCCGCACAUCACCUCCAGGCCCUCAGAACACCUGCCCCAGCCCCACCAUGCUCAUGGCGUCCACCACUUCCGCUGUGCCUGGGCAUCCCUCUCUGCCCAGCCUGCCCAGCAACAGCAGCCAGGAGAGGCCACUGGACACCCGGGACCCGCUGCUAGCCCGGGCGGAGCUGGCGCUGCUCUCCAUAGUCUUUGUGGCUGUGGCCCUGAGCAAUGGCCUGGUGCUGGCGGCCCUAGCUCGGCGGGGCCGGCGGGGCCACUGGGCACCCAUACACGUCUUCAUUGGCCACUUGUGCCUGGCCGACCUGGCCGUGGCUCUGUUCCAAGUGCUGCCCCAGCUGGCCUGGAAGGCCACCGACCGCUUCCGUGGGCCAGAUGCCCUGUGUCGGGCCGUGAAGUAUCUGCAGAUGGUGGGCAUGUAUGCCUCCUCCUACAUGAUCCUGGCCAUGACGCUGGACCGCCACCGUGCCAUCUGCCGUCCCAUGCUGGCGUACCGCCAUGGAAGUGGGGCUCACUGGAACCGGCCGGUGCUAGUGGCUUGGGCCUUCUCGCUCCUUCUCAGCCUGCCCCAGCUCUUCAUCUUCGCCCAGCGCAACGUGGAAGGUGGCAGCGGGGUCACUGACUGCUGGGCCUGCUUUGCGGAGCCCUGGGGCCGUCGCACCUAUGUCACCUGGAUUGCCCUGAUGGUGUUCGUGGCACCUACCCUGGGUAUCGCCGCCUGCCAGGUGCUCAUCUUCCGGGAGAUUCAUGCCAGUCUGGUGCCAGGGCCAUCAGAGAGGCCUGGGGGGCGCCGCAGGGGACGCCGGACAGGCAGCCCCGGUGAGGGAGCCCACGUGUCAGCAGCUGUGGCCAAGACUGUGAGGAUGACGCUAGUGAUUGUGGUCGUCUAUGUGCUGUGCUGGGCACCCUUCUUCCUGGUGCAGCUGUGGGCCGCGUGGGACCCGGAGGCACCUCUGGAAGGUGGGUGUAGCCGUGGCUAGGGCUGACGGGGCCACUUGGGCUUGGCCGCAUGCCCCUGUGCCCCACCAGCCAUCCUGAACCCAACCUAGAUCCUCCACCUCCACAGGGGCGCCCUUUGUGCUACUCAUGUUGCUGGCCAGCCUCAACAGCUGCACCAACCCCUGGAUCUAUGCAUCUUUCAGCAGCAGCGUGUCCUCAGAGCUGCGAAGCUUGCUCUGCUGUGCCCGGGGACGCACCCCACCCAGCCUGGGUCCCCAAGAUGAGUCCUGCACCACCGCCAGCUCCUCCCUGGCCAAGGACACUUCAUCGUGAGGAGCUGUUGGGUGUCUUGCCUCUAGAGGCUUUGAGAAGCUCAGCUGCCUUCCUGGGGCUGGUCCUGGGAGCCACUGGGAGGGGGACCCGUGGAGAAUUGGCCAGAGCCUGUGGCCCCGAGGCUGGGACACUGUGUGGCCCUGGACAAGCCACAGCCCCUGCCUGGGUCUCCACAUCCCCAGCUGUAUGAGGAGAGCUUCAGGCCCCAGGACUGUGGGGGCCCCUCAGGUCAGCUCACUGAGCUGGGUGUAGGAGGGGCUGCAGCAGAGGCCUGAGGAGUGGCAGGAAAGAGGGAGCAGGUGCCCCCAGGUGAGACAGCGGUCCCAGGGGCCUGAAAAGGAAGGACCAGGCUGGGGCCAGGGGACCUUCCUGUCUCCGCCUUUCUAAUCCCUCCCUCCUCAUUCUCUCCCUAAUAAAAAUUGGAGCUCAUUUUCCACA